GCCUUGCACACUCAGAAACAAACAAGAGAGAUGGUCACGGCGGCCAAGUCUGCAGUUCACCUCUGUGGCCACUUCCCUCUGGAUGAAGCCCUCAGCCAUGGUCUCCUCUUCACGAGAUUAUAAGGAAAGAUAAUUCAGAUGGAAAUCUUUUUUACCCAGCCUGCUGGAAAUGCAAUGAUUGUUGCUACAAGGAUUGAAGGCAAUGGGCUGGAAACACGCACCCAGCUCAGACCCUGCCUUCGGUCGGUGCCGGAAUCCUUCCUUGACCCCAGCCUCACCGUGAGACACCGGGCCCUUCACUCAGAAAGGGCUCCGUCAGUCAGCACCUUGGCGGCCCACUACCCACCGUCCACCUGAUGGACUGCCCAGCUCCAUUCUUCUGGGGUGUGUGGGAGCUUGUCCGGGGUGCAGGGCAAGGCAAUGUGAGAGCCAGCGGGGGCUCUGCUGGACACAGGCCAUGCCCGGGCAGCCUGGCGAUGCUUGGGUCAGUCCCCUUGUCCCACUGGAGGCCCAGAUGGACACCACUUGCUCUCCCUCCUCCUACCAUCGUGAGAUAGAAUGAAAUUAAAGGUACUGCAGCAGCUCUGGGCUCUCCGUGGUUCAGCUGUGAGGACACAGUGGGGCCACAGCACAGCCCUCCUCAGCAGUGGUACCUCCAUAGCAGUGGUGCCUGCUGUGUCUCAGAAUUGUUGCAGGAGGCUGUGCUCACAAAAAUGCCAUGCACCGUGGGUGGGGGACACUGGGGAACAAUGGGCUGGUGACCCUCAGAGUUCUUUGGAACUACCUGUGGCUGCAGCUGCCCCCUUACCAUGUGAACUUCAGGACGCUUCUCUGUCAAGCAAGGCUCUUAGAAGAACGUGGUCCCGUGACAGUCCCGAGAGCGGCUCACAGAUGGCUCCAUCUCCCUCCUUCCGAGCACACCGUGGGUUCACAUUUCACUGUGGUGUGACCACCUGGCAUGCUUUAGUGGGAGUGGUGUGACCAGAGCACGCCGGGCCCCACCAAAUCUCCCCUCUGCACGCAGCGGCAGCAUGGAAACGGUGGCUGCCCCAUCAGCCUGGGACCCUGCAUGGUCAGGAUGAGCACAGCCCCUUGACAAAGCUUGGGAUGGGGGCCUGUCUGUUACUGCAUUAACCAGCCUGCACCAAUUCAGAGUCUUCUCAACUUUCAGUUUUGGAUAUAUGCAAUCUUGCGUGAACUUAUGCAUGGAGCGGAGAAUCUAAUGUACCCAUAGCUAUGGAUCUCCCGAGCACAGAUCAUGCCAAAGGUGGAGGUUGAGAGGCAGACACAGGCACUGGACAUUGAUGGAGAAGUGAGGGAAGGUGAGCAAUGAAUGUGAUGUGGACUGACACGUAAUUUGGAAACUACUAGAAGGCUCUUGAAUGGAACCAGGGAUUCUUCACACUUCAUAGAGCAGCUGAAAGGGACUUGAGCACUACUUGGGCCUUCUGACGCCAGAGUUACAGAAUGCUCUUUUGCCAAAUCAUGGAUGGCCACUCGAGCACACAGAUAUUCAGGAUCCUCUUGUCCCCGUGUGCAGAGAGGCCUGGUGCUGGAUAUCGUUUAUAGGCUGGACUGCAUGUGGACCCCGAUGACAUGGCACUUUGUUUCUGACCAGUCAGGACACACAAGAGGCCCGGCGCAAACACAACAAAGCCCGCAGACAUUCUGUCCCCACGAAGAACGGACGCCACUCGACUUCCUAGCAUCUUGACGGGCUAUCCAAGCGCGGAGUCAGUUUAUAAGAAUGAGAGCGCUCGCUGUGCUGUCUGUCACGCUGGUUAUGGCCUGCACAGAAGCCUUCUUCCCCUUCAUCUCGAGAGGGAAAGAACUCCUUUGGGGAAAGCCUGAGGAGUCUCGUGUCUCUAGCGUCUUGGAGGAAAGCAAGCGCCUGGUGGACACCGCCAUGUACGCCACGAUGCAGAGAAACCUCAAGAAAAGAGGAAUCCUUUCUCCAGCUCAGCUUCUGUCUUUUUCCAAACUUCCUGAGCCAACAAGCGGAGUGAUUGCCCGAGCAGCAGAGAUAAUGGAAACAUCAAUACAAGCGAUGAAAAGAAAAGUCAACCUGAAAACUCAACAAUCACAGCAUCCAACGGAUGCUUUAUCAGAAGAUCUGCUGAGCAUCAUUGCAAACAUGUCUGGAUGUCUCCCUUACAUGCUGCCCCCAAAAUGCCCAAACACUUGCCUGGCGAACAAAUACAGGCCCAUCACAGGAGCUUGCAACAACAGAGACCACCCCAGAUGGGGCGCCUCCAACACGGCCCUGGCACGAUGGCUCCCUCCAGUCUAUGAGGACGGCUUCAGUCAGCCCCGAGGCUGGAACCCCGGCUUCUUGUACAACGGGUUCCCACUGCCCCCGGUCCGGGAGGUGACAAGACAUGUCAUUCAAGUUUCAAAUGAGGUUGUCACAGAUGAUGACCGCUAUUCUGACCUCCUGAUGGCAUGGGGACAAUACAUCGACCACGACAUCGCGUUCACACCACAGAGCACCAGCAAAGCUGCCUUCGGGGGAGGGGCUGACUGCCAGAUGACUUGUGAGAACCAAAACCCAUGUUUUCCCAUACAACUCCCGGAGGAGGCCCGGCCGGCCGCGGGCACCGCCUGUCUGCCCUUCUACCGCUCUUCGGCCGCCUGCGGCACCGGGGACCAAGGCGCGCUCUUUGGGAACCUGUCCACGGCCAACCCGCGGCAGCAGAUGAACGGGUUGACCUCGUUCCUGGACGCGUCCACCGUGUAUGGCAGCUCCCCGGCCCUAGAGAGGCAGCUGCGGAACUGGACCAGUGCCGAAGGGCUGCUCCGCGUCCACGCGCGCCUCCGGGACUCCGGCCGCGCCUACCUGCCCUUCGUGCCGCCACGCGCGCCUGCGGCCUGUGCGCCCGAGCCCGGCAUCCCCGGAGAGACCCGCGGGCCCUGCUUCCUGGCCGGAGACGGCCGCGCCAGCGAGGUCCCCUCCCUGACGGCACUGCACACGCUGUGGCUGCGCGAGCACAACCGCCUGGCCGCGGCGCUCAAGGCCCUCAAUGCGCACUGGAGCGCGGACGCCGUGUACCAGGAGGCGCGCAAGGUCGUGGGCGCUCUGCACCAGAUCAUCACCCUGAGGGAUUACAUCCCCAGGAUCCUGGGACCCGAGGCCUUCCAGCAGUACGUGGGUCCCUAUGAAGGCUAUGACUCCACCGCCAACCCCACUGUGUCCAACGUGUUCUCCACAGCCGCCUUCCGCUUCGGCCAUGCCACGAUCCACCCGCUGGUGAGGAGGCUGGACGCCAGCUUCCAGGAGCACCCCGACCUGCCCGGGCUGUGGCUGCACCAGGCUUUCUUCAGCCCAUGGACAUUACUCCGUGGAGGUGGUUUGGACCCACUAAUACGAGGCCUUCUUGCAAGACCAGCCAAACUGCAGGUGCAGGAUCAGCUGAUGAACGAGGAGCUGACGGAAAGGCUCUUUGUGCUGUCCAAUUCCAGCACCUUGGAUCUGGCGUCCAUCAACCUGCAGAGGGGCCGGGACCACGGGCUGCCAGGUUACAAUGAGUGGAGGGAGUUCUGCGGCCUGCCUCGCCUGGAGACCCCCGCUGACCUGAGCACAGCCAUCGCCAGCAGGAGCGUGGCCGACAAGAUCCUGGACUUGUACAAGCAUCCUGACAACAUCGAUGUCUGGCUGGGAGGCUUAGCUGAAAACUUCCUCCCCAGGGCUCGGACAGGGCCCCUGUUUGCCUGUCUCAUUGGGAAGCAGAUGAAGGCUCUGCGGGACGGUGACUGGUUUUGGUGGGAGAACAGCCACGUCUUCACGGAUGCACAGAGGCGUGAGCUGGAGAAGCACUCCCUGUCUCGGGUCAUCUGUGACAACACUGGCCUCACCAGGGUGCCCAUGGAUGCCUUCCAAGUCGGCAAAUUCCCCGAAGACUUUGAGUCUUGUGACAGCAUCACUGGCAUGAACCUGGAGGCCUGGAGGGAAACCUUUCCUCAAGACGACAAGUGUGGCUUCCCAGAGAGCGUGGAGAAUGGGGACUUUGUGCACUGUGAGGAGUCUGGGAGGCGCGUGCUGGUGUAUUCCUGCCGGCACGGGUAUGAGCUCCAAGGCCGGGAGCAGCUCACUUGCACCCAGGAAGGAUGGGAUUUCCAGCCUCCCCUCUGCAAAGACUCCGGGAGGCUCCCUCGGGUGACUUGGAUCUCCAUGUCGCUGGCUGCUCUGCUGAUCGGAGGCUUCGCAGGUCUCACCUCGACGGUGAUUUGCAGGUGGACACGCACUGGCACUAAAUCCACACUGCCCAUCUCGGAGACAGGCGGAGGAACUCCCGAGCUGAGAUGCGGAAAGCACCAGGCCGUAGGGACCUCACCGCAGCGGGCCGCAGCUCAGGACUCGGAGCAGGUGGGCCACACCAUGCCGCAUGUUUCCAGCUGCCACCGCAGUGGUUGGACAGGAUCUGGGUGUCGGAGCAGCUCUGCUGGGGCUCCCUGCAUAUUUCUGUUUACUCCGUGUUUCCUAGUCCGUUCUGCACCUUCCUCCGGGAGGUUUUAUUUACAAGCUAAUGACAGUGAGCCAGAAUGUGAGCCUGCUUAGUGAGAGGAAUGAAGAUGCCUUCCAUUUGUACAAACCGGUUCCAAAACUAAGGGCUCACUUUCAGGCGUUUGCUUCCACUUAAUCUGAGGAUCGGCUGGAAGCACAGGAGAGGAAGGAGAAGCUGAAGCAAAACCCUGACUUUUAAAUUCUGAUUUUUAAGUGGAAUAGUUAUAAUCAGUGUGGAAAAAUGUGUAUGUUUAUGUUUUACCCCCUUACCUUGUAUGCAGAACCCCAAGGGAGGCCAUAUCAAAAACUCACUUGUGUAAGUCUGACUUUUGAACUGAGAGAAGCAGAGAGCAGAACAGUGGCCUCCAGAGGGGAGUGGGGAGGUGCUGGUCACAGGCACAAAGUCUCAGGCAGGAGGAGGGCGCCUCAGGUCUGCUGCACGGCAUGGGGCGCACGCUUCCUCAUAAUGAUCGCAUGUUUCAAAAUUGCUAAAACAAUAGGUUUUUUUUUUUUUGAGAUAGAGUCUUGCUCUGUCGCCCAGACUGGAGUGCAGUGGCACAAACAUAGCUCACUGCAGCUUCGACCCUCCUGCUCAAGCAAUCCUCUUGCCUCAGCCUCUUGCGUGGCUGGGUCUACAGGCGCUCACCACCAUGCCUGGCUAAUUUUUAAAUUUUUUACAGAGAUGCAGCCUCGCUAUGCUGCCCAGGCUGGUGUUGAGCCCUUAGGCCCAAGAGAUCCUCCAGUCUGAAACUCCCAAAGUGCUGGGACCACAGCCACCCACUAAAAUAAUAGAUUUUAAAUGUUCUAACUGCCAAAAAAAGAUGUGAGGUGAUAUGUUAAUUAAUUUGAUAUAAUCUCUCCACAAUGUAAAGGUAUCAAAACCAUGUUUAAAACAUAAAUAUAUGCAGUUAGUAUUUGUCAACUAAAAAUACAAAUUUUAAUUUAAACAAAGUCACUUACUUGCAUA